ACAGAACUCCCACGGACACACCAUGAUAAGGACGCUGCUGCUGUCCACUUUGGUGGCUGGAGCCCUCAGUUGUGGGGACCCCACUUACCCACCUUAUGUGACUAGGGUGGUUGGCGGUGAAGAAGCGAGGCCCAACAGCUGGCCCUGGCAGGUCUCCCUGCAGUACAGCUCCAAUGGCAAGUGGUACCACACCUGCGGAGGGUCCCUGAUAGCCAACAGCUGGGUCCUGACGGCUGCCCACUGCAUCAGCUCCUCCAGGACCUACCGCGUGGGGCUGGGCCGGCACAACCUCUACGUUGCGGAGUCCGGCUCGCUGGCAGUCAGUGUCUCUAAGAUUGUGGUGCACAAGGACUGGAACUCCAACCAAAUCUCCAAAGGGAACGACAUUGCCCUGCUCAAACUGGCUAACCCCGUCUCCCUCACCGACAAGAUCCAGCUGGCCUGCCUCCCUCCUGCCGGCACCAUUCUACCCAACAACUACCCCUGCUACGUCACGGGCUGGGGAAGGCUGCAGACCAACGGGGCUGUUCCUGAUGUCCUGCAGCAGGGCCGGUUGCUGGUUGUGGACUAUGCCACCUGCUCCAGCUCUGCCUGGUGGGGCAGCAGCGUGAAAACCAGUAUGAUCUGUGCUGGGGGUGAUGGCGUGAUCUCCAGCUGCAACGGAGACUCUGGCGGGCCACUGAACUGUCAGGCGUCUGACGGCCGGUGGCAGGUGCACGGCAUCGUCAGCUUCGGGUCUCGCCUCGGCUGCAACUACUACCACAAGCCCUCCGUCUUCACGCGGGUCUCCAAUUACAUCGACUGGAUCAAUUCGGUGAUUGCAAAUAACUAACCAAAAGAAGUCCCUGGGACUGUUUCAGACUUGGAAAGGUCACAGAAGGAAAAUAAUAUAAUAAAGUGACAACUAUGCAAAUCA